GAAAGGGAAAUGGGGCAAGAUGGCUGGAGAAAUCCGAACGCGCCCGGGGGCGCGGCGGCGGUGGCGCAGGCGGGGCAGGGCGGGCGGCGGCCCUGGUUGCGGCACCUUAGCGCGGGGAGGCGGCCCCUCCCACCUCUGCCCCGGAGCCGGCAGGGAGACCGCCGCCAAGUUCGGGCCCCAGCUGCAGGCAUCUGAAGCCUAGACCCAUCCAUGCCGCGUUCGCCUAUCUUUUUUGGAAAUAUCGAAGGAACCGACUUUGAACUCCAGAGGGAUCUUUUCUUUGGAGGUUCCCCGAUGCAGCCCUCAAGAUGCAUCCGCACUCCACACCUAGGAAUUGCCCGCGCCCAUAGAGGGCAGGAGUGCGGCCCUUUGUACUGGCCAAGAGUCAGCGAAUAGAGAAUUUGCAGCCCAGAGGCAAUGGGUUAUUUCCCUGUCGGGGUGGGCCCCAGCCGAUUUCUGCACCUUUUUGGGUAUCCAGGCAUAACCCUCACUAUGUUUCACUGACUCCUGCGUUUGCAAAGUCCCUUAAGGUAGAAUGACCCUAUUUUCUGAACCAGCUCGUGGACAGAACCUUUGAAUUUGGAAAAUCCAGGCAAUGGGCCUACUGAGCCAACCGCUCCGCCCAUGCUUAACUGGCUUCUAGCACCCAUUCCAGUUGAAGAUGGAGUCCACAGCCUACCCUCUCAAUUUGAGCCUGAAAGAAGAGGAAGAGGAAGAAGAGAUUCAGAGCCGGGAACUAGAGGACGGCCCGGCAGACAUGCAGAAAGUACGAAUCUGCUCUGAGGGCGGAUGGGUACCGGCCCUAUUUGAUGAGGUGGCCAUAUAUUUUUCCGAUGAGGAAUGGGAAGUUUUGACGGAGCAACAAAAGGCCCUCUACCGGGAAGUCAUGAGGAUGAAUUAUGAAACUGUCCUGUCCCUGGAAUUCCCAUUCCCUAAGCCAGACAUGAUCACCCGUUUGGAAGGGGAGGAGGAGUCUCAGAAUUCUGACGAGUGGCAGCUCCAAGGAGGCACCUCUGCAGAAAAUGAAGAAUCUGACGUAAAGCCUCCAGACUGGCCAAACCCAAUGAAUGCUACCUCCCAGUUUCCUCAGCCUCAGCACUUUGACAGCUUUGGCCUCCGUCUGCCUCGGGAUAUCACAGAGCUGCCCGAGUGGAGUGAGGGGUACCCCUUCUACAUGGCCAUGGGCUUCCCAGGGUAUGACCUCUCGGCUGAUGACAUAGCUGGGAAGUUUCAGUUCAGCCGGGGCAUGCGCCGCAGUUACGACGCAGGGUUCAAGCUGAUGGUAGUGGAAUAUGCUGAGAGUACCAACAACUGCCAGGCUGCCAAGCAGUUUGGAGUAUUGGAAAAAAACGUUCGAGACUGGCGCAAAGUGAAGCCACAGCUUCAAAACGCCCACGCCAUGCGGCGGGCAUUCCGAGGCCCCAAGAAUGGGAGGUUUGCUCUGGUGGACCAGCGUGUGGCCGAAUAUGUCAGAUACAUGCAGGCCAAAGGGGACCCCAUCACCCGGGAGGCGAUGCAGCUGAAAGCUCUCGAAAUCGCCCAGGAAAUGAACAUUCCAGAGAAAGGGUUCAAGGCAAGCUUGGGUUGGUGUCGAAGAAUGAUGAGAAGGUAUGACCUGUCUCUGAGGCAUAAAGUGCCCGUGCCCCAGCACCUGCCGGAAGACCUGACUGAGAAACUCGUCACUUACCAGCGCAGUGUCCUGGCUCUGCGCAGGGCGCAUGACUAUGAGGUAGCUCAGAUGGGGAAUGCAGAUGAGACGCCCAUUUGUUUAGAGGUGCCAUCACGGGUAACUGUUGAUAACCAGGGCGAAAAGCCUGUCUUGGUCAAGACACCAGGCAGGGAAAAACUGAAAAUCACAGCAAUGCUUGGUGUCUUGGCUGAUGGGAGGAAGUUACCACCGUACAUCAUUUUGAGGGGAACAUAUAUCCCCCCGGGGAAGUUUCCCAGUGGGAUGGAAAUUCGCUGCCACCGGUAUGGGUGGAUGACUGAAGACUUGAUGCAGGACUGGUUGGAAGUGGUGUGGAGACGGAGGACAGGAGCAGUGCCCAAGCAGCGAGGGAUGCUGAUCUUGAAUGGCUUCCGGGGCCAUGCCACAGAUUCCGUGAAGAACUCCAUGGAAAGCAUGAACACUGACAUGGUGAUCAUCCCAGGGGGUCUGACCUCACAGCUUCAGGUGCUGGAUGUCGUGGUCUACAAGCCACUGAAUGACAGUGUGCGGGCCCAGUACUCCAACUGGCUUCUGGCUGGGAACCUGGCGCUGAGCCCAACCGGGAAUGCUAAGAAGCCACCCCUGGGCCUCUUUCUGGAGUGGGUCAUGGUCGCGUGGAAUAGCAUCUCAAGUGAGUCCAUCGUCCAAGGGUUCAAGAAGUGCCAUAUCUCCAGCAACUUGGAGGAGGAAGACGAUGUCCUGUGGGAAAUCGAGAGUGAGUUGCCAGGAGGAGGAGAACCACCAAAAGAUUGUGACACCGAAAGCAUGGCUGAGAGCAACUGAAGGGAAAGGGAAAGGUAACCACUCAGGAGUAGAUACUCAGUGCCUUUGCUGACAUGUCUGUGUUCUACAAACACCUUCUCUCCAUUAUUUUUCUGUUUUUAAGUUCCCUUAGAGCCUACAGUGCAGUAGUGUAGAUCAGGGGUCCCCAACCCCCAGGUCACGGACCAUACUGGUCCAUGGCCUGUCAGGAACUGGGCUGCACAGCAGGAGGUGAGCGGCAGGUGAGCAAGCAUUACCACCUGAGCUCCGCCCGCUGUCACAGCAGCGGCAUUAGAUUCUCAUAGGAGCACAAACCCUGUUGUGAACUGCACAUGUGAGGGAUCUAGGUUGCAGGCUCCUCAAUGCCUGAGGAUCUGAGGCGGAACAGUUUCAUCCCAAAGCCAUCCUACCACCCACUACCCCGCACUUCCUGGGUCCCUGCAAAAAUUGUCUUCCAUGAAACCAGUCCCUGGUGCCAGAAAAGUUGGGGACUGCUGGUAUAGAUAACAGACCAUUAGCAUUUUCUCCUUUAUAUGAAACAUUUAUUAUUUGAUUUAUUUGUGUCUAUUUUGCUCUGUGGCUUGGACCCAGAAACACUUGUAUAAUAGGUGAAAUGAACAAAGAAUGAGCUGCCAGAACAUCUGAGAGCUGUAAAGUUAAAAUUAUUUGGACCCAAAGAAGCAUAGUCUGACGUUGUUCAGUUCACACAAAAUUUUGUCUGAAAAGCCAACUUUUUUCUUUCCCUUUUAAAUUAUGCUGAACAUUUAGGGCCAGUAUGUGUAACUGACAUGCUGGGACAGUUGUACUCACUUUUGCUGGCCUGUAGGACUGUGACAUAGGGAGAACACUAAGUGUGUCCUCCGGGCCUCGGGUCUCAGUCCUGGAGCUAUCUACAGUAUGUUACCAGCGAGUAAGAAUAAUAGCUUCUACUUGCUUUUCCCUACAGAGUUCAGGAGUUUUAAAACGUCAUCUUAGUCUCAUUAUGACCUUCACAUGGGCUAUGACAAUAAUUUCCUGUAGUCAGCAGAUGUCUGAAGGAAGAUAUUUUUUAACUGAAUCUUUACACCAAAAAAAGAAAAUAAAACGGUGCGUAUCUAGGACUCUAGUGAGGGCUGAGGACAAUAGGCCUGGAAUUUUCUGGGUUGAGUACACAAGAAGAACAGCUUUCAAAGGAAAGUAGGAAUGGAGGCCUAACUGAGACAACACUAGUGAAAUGACCCCACCCACCUACACCUCCAGAGAGGAGGAGGAUGAGCAUGUACAGCAGGGGGGACACCCACAAAGAACAAACAAUUCAUUUACCUGUUCGUUCUCAUCUCCCUAAUUAUAAAUUAAAUUGAUCCUCCAGACAGUGUUUUAUAUGAAGGAAGAAGCCACCUUUUUUACAGAGGACCUGAAACCGUCAACCAUCUUCACACAUUCUUUUUCUUUCUUUUAAAGUAUAAUUAGGUAUUUCCAUCUUCCUUGCUUUUUUCUCCAAAUGAAAUGCUAAUGGGAGCCUUAUUUUACCCACUUCAGCUAUAUAAGUCCAUCUGUGUUUCAAAGAGUGACUUAUGUCUCCUGCCUUGCUUCCAAAUUAAAUUGUACUCAUAUUGCUGAAUCCCAUUGUAAUUCUGGGAUCCCUGGAAUUACAAUGGAGCAAGAAGUUCUUACUAUUACAUUCAAAAUCACCAAAAUUGCUUUUUUUUCCCCCUUGGGUCCUCCUUGCUUUGAGAAACCCCAUGAAUCCAGCCUCCCUUUUCUGCUGACCCUUAUAUUGCCUGCAUUGGAUAUCAAACUGAAUUACAUUGAGUUUCCAUCUUUUCUUCAUUUACCUUUUGCUUUUCCCUCUCCUUGUUAGAUAACAUUUUUGUGCACUUUUAAUUUCCUAAGCUCCUUACCACCUCAGGGACAUGAUUAAAAACUUCCAGAAGAGGAAAGGAGAAAAAGCUAUGCUAAGUUGCAUUUAUGAAUGUUGGCCUGUAAUAUUGGUCAUGAGCUUUUGCUCUUCUAGUCUGCCACAAUUCUCUCUGCAGCUCCUGAGGAAGUGAUGGGAGUAGACAGAUUCACAGUGAACAAGAGAUUUGGGAGACCAAGUGGGCAUAAAACUACGUCUUGGCCUCUAUUUGGAAAUCUGAAUGAUGGAAUUAUUAUGUUUGUUAAAAGUUAUACCAAAAAGCCAAGGGUUAAUUCAUUUAGGUUCUCUCUGUUUUCCAGCAAAUGGAACUCUGAUUUAAACAGCUGGGGAUGAAAUUCCUCAAGAUGAUUAUUCCUGAAAGUGUGGAUGCGCUGGAUGCGCAGGGAACAUCAGGAAAAGGCCACGGGGCUCUGAACAGCCCCGGUCCAGACAGCAGCCUGUACAUCCAUCCCAGGACACAGCCCAGCCCCUCCCCACACCAUACAAGGUAUCAGAAAAGUCUAGGACCUAUCAUUUCAUCAGAGACAUGAUCAGAAAAGAAACUGCUUCUGCCCCAUUUCUUGUUUUGGAGAUUACUCCAUCUGUCCAUCAAAAGAAACCUGUAAAUAUGAAAGAACAAAGGUUAUUUCCUGGAGAAAAGACAAUUUAUUCAACACCAACGAGGGACUCAUCAUAUGGGCACAACUCUGGUGUCCUUCUAUGGAGAAAACCUCAAGUAAAGUUUUAUUCUGCCUUUGAAAAUGCUUCCAAAAGUAGACCCUGUCCCCACACAGGUCAAGACUACAGAGAAGGCUUUGUAGAAAUGUGUCACCUAUGUACACCUGCUACUUACACAUUUCCUCUUUUGGAAAAAUGAGAUACUUAGAAUAACAAGAAAAUUAAGACAUACUGGCCUGGUGCCAGCAGAUGGCUUUUCUAUAGACAAACUAGGUUAGUGUGGAAGAUAUAGGUUAAAAUAAACUAUGCUGUUUUAUUUAUCUUCCCAACCUGAUUGGCAGCUAGACUUUUUUAGGGUCUCAUUUAAUGGCCCUGUUUUUUUCAUUAUUAUAUUUAAUGAUAGGGCAGGAUUUCGUAUGCAAGCUCUUGUUUCUCAGGCUGCCUGCAGAAGAAGUCGCUAUAAAUUAUCUGUUGUCUACAUGGUACAAGGCCCAUUGACUCAUCUGAUGCUUGUUUUGUUAAUUUCUUUAAUAUUUUUAUCACGGGGCAGUGGGAGGGCUUGGGCUUUUAGCCACAGCUGUUUUAAGACUUCUGAUCUCCUGCCCUGCAGGAAUAGGUGGGAAGUCAUUGAAUUUUUACACUAUAGUAAUUUGCAUUCCCACAUAAGUUUGAGUGUUACGAAAACAUUCCUUUAAAGGGAUCUGUGCUACACAAAAUAUGCCAGGACCUCACAGACAAAGCCAUUGCUAGAAAUGUCAUUCCAAUGAUCAGAUCUGGAAACAGGCUGCCAUAACCACUUUUCCUUCUUGUAGACUCAGCUCACCUGUAUAUUUAAACUGUUCUUGGCAUCUUGAAACACCUAUUUCUACUCAGGUACUCAUUGUCCUGUUACUGAUUCACCUUUCUGAUCCUUUUCAACCAGUUUUCCCCCAAGGGGGGAAAUUUUACUUAACCUCUAGUAUUUGAACAACUCAAUAUUUGAAUUGUUGCCCCAUUUGCUUUUACCUGUACUGUAUUCUUGGUCAUCUCAAAUGGCGUCUAAACCCAGCUACUUUGCAUUCCAGAAGUUUCCAUUCCCUCCAAUUCCACCUAAUUUUUCAUCUGUCCUAGUUACUGGCUCUUUCUUCAUGUCUUAUUUCUCUUGCUUUGGGAGCUUAAAAGAUUUUACAAGACCUAAUUUUGGGUUCCUUCCUUGGAGCCAUAGUUACCCUGCCAAGAAGAGUAGAAAAUGGGUUCAACUCCUGUUUCGCUCCACCAACACCUCUGUGAGUCUCAUCAUCAGCUGAGCGAUGAUGCCUUACAGGUUGCAUAGCACUGGAACUUUCCUAGAGUAACGGCUCUGCUGCCAGGGUUUCUCUGGGCUCAUUCUUCCACUGACUUAAUUAUGAUCUAUGCCUAACAGAGCCCCAGUACAACUAUUUUGCAGAAUGGCUGUUACCCUAGAAUUACUAUAGCACAUAUUGAGAUAUAGUUGUACUCCCUAGUAGAUAGGAACUGACCCCAACAAUAAACUUUGAUAAUAAAGACAA